AUGAUGGGACAAAAUCAAACCAGCAUCUCAGACUUCCUGCUCCUGGGCCUGCCCAUCCAACCAGAGCAGCAAAACCUGUGCUAUGCCCUGUUCUUGGCCAUGUAUCUUACCACCCUCCUGGGGAACCUCCUCAUCAUUGUCCUCAUUCGACUGGACUCCCAUCUCCACACGCCUGUGUAUUUGUUUCUCAGCAACUUGUCCUUCUCUGACCUCUGCUUUUCCUCAGUCACAAUGCCCAAAUUGCUGCAGAACAUGCAGAACCAAGACCCAUCCAUCCCCUAUGCAGACUGCCUGACCCAAAUGUACUUCUUCUUGUAUUUUUCGGAUCUAGAGAGCUUCCUCCUUGUGGCCAUGGCCUAUGACCGCUAUGUGGCCAUCUGCUUCCCCAUGCACUACACCGCCAUCUGCUUCCUCCUGCACUACACCGCCAUCAUGAGCCCCAUGCUCUGUCUCUCCGUGGUGGCGCUGUCCUGGGUGCUGACCACCUUCCAUGCCAUGUUACACACUUUACUCAUGGCCAGGUUGUGUUUUUGUGCAGACAAUGUGAUCCCCCACUUUUUCUGUGAUAUGUCUGCUCUGCUGAAGCUGGCCUGCUCUGACACUCGAGUUAAUGAAUGGGUGAUAUUUAUCAUGGGAGGGCUCAUUCUUGUCAUCCCAUUCCUACUCAUCCUUGGGUCCUAUGCAAGAAUUGUCUCCUCCAUCCUCAAGGUCCCUUCUUCUAAGGGUAUCUGCAAGGCCUUCUCUACUUGUGGCUCCCACCUCUCUGUGGUGUCACUGUUCUAUGGGACCGUUAUUGGUCUCUACUUAUGCCCAUCAGCUAAUAGUUCUACUCUAAAGGACACUGUCAUGGCUAUGAUGUACACUGUGGUGACCCCUAUGCUGACCCCCUUCAUCUACAGCCUGAGGAACAGAGACAUGAAGGGAGCCCUGGAAAGGGUCAUUUGUAAAAGGAAAAAUCCCUUCCUUCUAUGA